AUUGCCUGCUUCUCCCCACCCCCAAAUUAAGUUGCUUAGCAAGGGGGAAAGAGGCUUUUUCCUUCUUCCAACAGCCCAGCCGAACGCCUUUCGUUUUUUGCCCCCGCGGACCUUCCAUGUAGGAAGCCGAGGCUGGCGAGCCCGACAUUCGGGAGCCACUGCGGGGGGGCCUCUUUUUGGGGAGGCGCCGACGGGGGCAGGCUCGGCCGUCCCCAGGGAAGCGGCGGCCGGGUUCCUCCGGGGCGCGCCGGGGCCGGAGAGCCGCGCAGGGCGCGGGCCGCGCGGGGUGGGGCAGCCGGAGCGCAGGCCCCCGAUCCCCGGCGGGCGCCCCCGGGCCCCCGCGCGCGCCCCGGCCUCCGGGAGACUGGCGCAUGCCACGGAGCGCCCCUCGGGCCGCCGCCGCUCCUGCCCGGGCCCCUGCUGCUGCUGCUGUCGCCUGCGCCUGCUGCCCCAACUCGGCGCCCGACUUCUUCAUGGUGUGCGGAGGUCAUGUUCGCUCCUUAGCAGGCAAACGACUUUUCUCCUCGCCUCCUCGCCCCGCAUGUUCAGGACCAAACGAUCUGCGCUCGUCCGGCGUCUCUGGAGGAGCCGUGCGCCCGGCGGCGAGGACGAGGAGGAGGGCGCAGGGGGAGGUGGAGGAGGAGGCGAGCUGCGGGGAGAAGGGGCGACGGACAGCCGAGCGCAUGGGGCCGGUGGCGGCGGCCCGGGCAGGGCUGGAUGCUGCCUGGGCAAGGCGGUGCGAGGUGCCAAAGGUCACCACCAUCCCCACCCGCCAGCCGCGGGCGCCGGCGCGGCCGGGGGCGCCGAGGCGGAUCUGAAGGCGCUCACGCACUCGGUGCUCAAGAAACUGAAGGAGCGGCAGCUGGAGCUGCUGCUCCAGGCCGUGGAGUCCCGCGGCGGGACGCGCACCGCGUGCCUCCUGCUGCCCGGCCGCCUGGACUGCAGGCUGGGCCCGGGGGCGCCCGCCGGCGCGCAGCCUGCGCAGCCGCCCUCGUCCUACUCGCUCCCCCUCCUGCUGUGCAAAGUGUUCAGGUGGCCGGAUCUCAGGCAUUCCUCGGAAGUCAAGAGGCUGUGUUGCUGUGAAUCUUACGGGAAGAUCAACCCCGAGCUGGUGUGCUGCAACCCCCAUCACCUUAGCCGACUCUGCGAACUAGAGUCUCCCCCCCCUCCUUACUCCAGAUACCCGAUGGAUUUUCUCAAACCAACUGCAGACUGUCCAGAUGCUGUGCCUUCCUCCGCUGAAACAGGGGGAACGAAUUAUCUGGCCCCUGGGGGGCUUUCAGAUUCCCAACUUCUUCUGGAGCCUGGGGAUCGGUCACACUGGUGCGUGGUGGCAUACUGGGAGGAGAAGACGAGAGUGGGGAGGCUCUACUGUGUCCAGGAGCCCUCUCUGGAUAUCUUCUAUGAUCUACCUCAGGGGAAUGGCUUUUGCCUCGGACAGCUCAAUUCGGACAACAAGAGUCAGCUGGUGCAGAAGGUGCGGAGCAAAAUCGGCUGCGGCAUCCAGCUGACGCGGGAGGUGGAUGGUGUGUGGGUGUACAACCGCAGCAGUUACCCCAUCUUCAUCAAGUCCGCCACACUGGACAACCCGGACUCCAGGACGCUGUUGGUACACAAGGUGUUCCCCGGUUUCUCCAUCAAGGCUUUCGACUACGAGAAGGCGUACAGCCUGCAGCGGCCCAAUGACCACGAGUUUAUGCAGCAGCCGUGGACGGGCUUUACCGUGCAGAUCAGCUUUGUGAAGGGCUGGGGCCAGUGCUACACCCGCCAGUUCAUCAGCAGCUGCCCGUGCUGGCUAGAGGUCAUCUUCAACAGCCGGUAGCCGCGUGCGGAGGGGACAGAGCGUGAGCUGAGCAGGCCACACUUCAAACUACUUUGCUGCUAAUAUUUUCCUCCUGAGUGCUUGCUUUUCAUGCAAACUCUUUGGUCGUUUUUUUUUUGUUUGUUGGUUGGUUUUCUUCUUCUCGUCCUCGUUUGUGUUCUGUUUUGUUUCGCUCUUUGAGAAAUAGCUUAUGAAAAGAAUUGUUGGGGGUUUUUUUGGAAGAAGGGGCAGGUAUGAUCGGCAGGACACCCUGAUAGGAAGAGGGGAAGCAGAAAUCCAAGCACCACCAAACACAGUGUAUGAAGGGGGGCGGUCAUCAUUUCACUUGUCAGGAGUGUGUGUGAGUGUGAGUGUGCGGCUGUGUGUGCACGCGUGUGCAGGAGCGGCAGAUGGGGAGACAACGUGCUCUUUGUUUUGUGUCUCUUAUGGAUGUCCCCAGCAGAGAGGUUUGCAGUCCCAAGCGGUGUCUCUCCUGCCCCUUGGACACGCUCAGUGGGGCAGAGGCAGUACCUGGGCAAGCUGGCGGCUGGGGUCCCAGCAGCUGCCAGGAGCACGGCUCUGUCCCCAGCCUGGGAAAGCCCCUGCCCCUCCUCUCCCUCAUCAAGGACACGGGCCUGUCCACAGGCUUCUGAGCAGCGAGCCUGCUAGUGGCCGAACCAGAACCAAUUAUUUUCAUCCUUGUCUUAUUCCCUUCCUGCCAGCCCCUGCCAUUGUAGCGUCUUUCUUUUUUGGCCAUCUGCUCCUGGAUCUCCCUGAGAUGGGCUUCCCAAGGGCUGCCGGGGCAGCCCCCUCACAGUAUUGCUCACCCAGUGCCCUCUCCCCUCAGCCUCUCCCCUGCCUGCCCUGGUGACAUCAGGUUUUUCCCGGACUUAGAAAACCAGCUCAGCACUGCCUGCUCCCAUCCUGUGUGUUAAGCUCUGCUAUUAGGCCAGCAAGCGGGGAUGUCCCUGGGAGGGACAUGCUUAGCAGUCCCCUUCCCUCCAAGAAGGAUUUGGUCCGUCAUAACCCAAGGUACCAUCCUAGGCUGACACCUAACUCUUCUUUCAUUUCUUCUACAACUCAUACACUCGUAUGAUACUUCGACACUGUUCUUAGCUCAAUGAGCAUGUUUAGACUUUAACAUAAGCUAUUUUUCUAACUACAAAGGUUUAAAUGAACAAGAGAAGCAUUCUCAUUGGAAAUUUAGCAUUGUAGUGCUUUGAGAGAGAAAGGACUCCUGAAAAAAAACCUGAGAUUUAUUAAAGAAAAAAAUGUAUUUUAUGUUAUAUAUAAAUAUAUUAUUACUUGUAAAUAUAAAGACGUUUUAUAAGCAUCAUUAUUUAUGUAUUGUGCAAUGUGUAUAAACAAGAAAAAUAAAGAAAAGAUGCACUUUGCUUUAAUAUAAAUGCAAAUAACAAAUGCCAAAUUAAAAAAGAUAAACACAAGAUUGGUGUUUUUUUCUAUGGGUGUUAUCACCUAGCUGAAUGUUUUUCUAAAGGAGUUUAUGUUCCAUUAAACGAUUUUUAAAAUGUACACUUGA